CGUGUUACUGGGCGAGGUUCCAGCCAAGGUGCCCACGCGCCUUGGGGGAAACCAGAGGACUUCUGCACCGUUUCCCGAGGACAGUUUGGCAGUGUUUCAGAAGGGCCUUAGAACCAGGCAGGCCCCCUUCUAGGAUGGUGGAAAGCCUAAAGAUCUGAAAACGGUCUCAAGUGUCGUCUUAGCGAUUGGCUGACUAAACCGAAUGCAAGCCGGAGACUGCACACGAUGUUGCCGUUAACAGUUACACUGGGCCGGGCAGUCAGAGGCAGGCGGAUCACCUGAGGUCAGGAGUUCGAGAACAGCCUGGCCAACAUGGCAUGAAGAACUCUUGACUGACAGAAACGGAGGGUGUGUCCAAAGUUUUGAGGACGGCCGAGCGGCGCUCCAAAACCCGUCCUCACAGCCUCGCCCCGUUCGCCUCAGCUACAACAAAUCAUCGUCAACCUGUUCCACCUUCUCCAGUCUGGUAGCAAAAAGGGGUGUCUCAGGCCACUCUUCACCUCCACCAUGAGCCUGGACAUCCAGAGCCUGGACAUCCAGUGUGAGGAGCUGAGCGACGCUAGAUGGGCCGAGCUCCUCCCUCUGCUCCAGCAGUGCCAAGUGGUCAGGCUGGACGACUGUGGCCUCACGGAAGCACGGUGCAAGGACAUCAGCUCUGCACUUCGAGUCAACCCUGCACUGGCAGAGCUCAACCUGCGCAGCAACGAGCUGGGCGAUGUCGGCGUGCAUUGCGUGCUCCAGGGCCUGCAGACCCCCUCCUGCAAGAUCCAGAAGCUGAGCCUCCAGAACUGCUGCCUGACGGGGGCCGGCUGCGGGGUCCUGUCCAGCACACUACGCACCCUGCCCACCCUGCAGGAGCUGCACCUCAGCGACAACCUCUUGGGGGAUGCGGGCCUGCAGCUGCUCUGCGAAGGACUCCUGGACCCCCAGUGCCGCCUGGAAAAGCUGCAGCUGGAGUAUUGCAGCCUCUCGGCUGCCAGCUGCGAGCCCCUGGCCUCCGUGCUCAGGGCCAAGCCGGACUUCAAGGAGCUCACGGUUAGCAACAACGACAUCAAUGAGGCUGGCGUCCGUGUGCUGUGCCAGGGCCUGAAGGACUCCCCCUGCCAGCUGGAGGCGCUCAAGCUGGAGAGCUGCGGUGUGACAUCAGACAACUGCCGGGACCUGUGCGGCAUUGUGGCCUCCAAGGCCUCGCUGCGGGAGCUGGCCCUGGGCAGCAACAAGCUGGGUGAUGUGGGCAUGGCGGAGCUGUGCCCAGGGCUGCUCCACCCCAGCUCCAGGCUCAGGACCCUGUGGAUCUGGGAGUGUGGCAUCACUGCCAAGGGCUGCGGGGAUCUGUGCCGUGUCCUCAGGGCCAAGGAGAGCCUGAAGGAGCUCAGCCUGGCCGGCAACGAGCUGGGGGAUGAGGGUGCCCGACUGCUGUGUGAGACCCUGCUGGAACCUGGCUGCCAGCUGGAGUCGCUGUGGGUGAAGUCCUGCAGCUUCACAGCCGCCUGCUGCUCCCACUUCAGCUCAGUGCUGGCCCAGAACAGGUUUCUCCUGGAGCUACAGAUAAGCAACAACAGGCUGGAGGAUGCGGGCGUGCGGGAGCUGUGCCAGGGCCUGGGCCAGCCUGGCUCUGUGCUGCGGGUGCUCUGGUUGGCCGACUGCGAUGUGAGUGACAGCAGCUGCAGCAGCCUCGCCGCAACCCUGUUGGCCAACCACAGCCUGCGUGAGCUGGACCUCAGCAACAACUGCCUGGGGGACGCCGGCAUCCUGCAGCUGGUGGAGAGCGUCCGGCAGCCGGGCUGCCUCCUGGAGCAGCUGGUCCUGUACGACAUUUACUGGUCUGAGGAGAUGGAGGACCGGCUGCAGGCCCUGGAGAAGGACAAGCCAUCCCUGAGGGUCAUCUCCUGAGGCUCUUCCUGCUGCUGCUCUCCCUGGACGACCGGCCUCGAGGCAACCCUGGGGCCCACCAGCCCCUGCCAUGCUCUCACCCUGCAUAUCCUAGGUUUGAAGAGAAACGCUCAGAUCCGCUUAUUUCUGCCAGUAUAUUUUGGACACUUUAUAAUCAUUAAAGCACUUUCUUGGCA